AUUCAUUCUCCCUGAAUCUUACCAACAAAACACUCCUGAGGAGAAAGAAAGAGAGGGAGGGAGAGAAAAAGAGAGAGAGAGAAACAAAAAACCAAAGAGAGAGAAAAAAUGAAUUCAUCUAAAUCAUCUGAAACACAAUGCACAGAGAGAGGAUGCUUCUCUUCCCAAAUGUUCUUAUGGACUGUUGCUGGGAUCCCCAUCCUAUUUCUCAGUGCCUGUUUCAUCACCAGAUGUGUUGUGACAUUUCGCAUCUUUCAAACCUGUGAUGAGAAAAAGUUUCAGCUACCUGAGAAUUUCACAGAGCUCUCCUGCUACAAUUAUGGAUCAGGUUCAGUCAAGAAUUGUUGUCCAUUGAACUGGGAAUAUUUUCAAUCCAGCUGCUACUUCUUUUCUACUGACACCAUUUCCUGGGCGUUAAGUUUAAAGAACUGCUCAGCCAUGGGGGCUCACCUGGUGGUUAUCAACUCACAGGAGGAGCAGGAAUUCCUUUCCUACAAGAAACCUAAAAUGAGAGAGUUUUUUAUUGGACUGUCAGACCAGGUUGUCGAGGGUCAGUGGCAAUGGGUGGACGGCACACCUUUGACAAAGUCUCUGAGCUUCUGGGAUGUAGGGGAGCCCAACAACAUAGCUACCCUGGAGGACUGUGCCACCAUGAGAGACUCUUCAAACCCAAGGCAAAAUUGGAAUGAUGUAACCUGUUUCCUCAAUUAUUUUCGGAUUUGUGAAAUGGUAGGAAUAAAUCCUUUGAACAAAGGAAAAUCUCUUUAAGAACAGAAGGCACAACUCAAAUGUGUAAAGAAGGAAGAGCAAGAACAUGGCCACACCCACCGCCCCACACGAGAAAUUUGUGCGCUGAACUUCAAAGGACUUCAUAAGUAUUUGUUACUCUGAUAUAAAUAAAAAUAAGUAGUUUUAAAUGUUAUAAUUCAUGUUACUGGCUGAAGUGCAUUUUCUCUCUACGUUAGUCUCAGGUCCUCUUCCCAGAAUUUACAAAGCAAUUCACUACCUUUUGCUACAUUUGCCUCAUUUUUUAGUGUUCGUAUGAAAGUACAGGGACACGGAGCCAAGACAGAGUCUAGCAAAGAAGGGGAUUUUGGAAGGUGCCUUCCAAAAAUCUCCUGAAUCCGGGCUCUGUAGCAGGUCCUCUUCUUUCUAGCUUCUGACAAGUCUGUCUUCUCUUCUUGGUUUCAUACCGUUCUUAUCUCCUGCCCAAGCAUAUAUCGUCUCUUUACUCCCCUGUAUAAUGAGUAAGAAGCUUCUUCAAGUCAUGAAACUUAUUCCUGCUCAGAAUACCGGUGUGGCCUUUCUGGCUACAGGCCUCCACUGCACCUUCUUAGGGAAGGGCAUGCCAGCCAUCAGCUCCAAACAGGCUGUAACCAAGUCCACCCAUCCCUGGGGCUUCCUUUGCUCUGCCUUAUUUUCAAUUGACUGAAUGGAUCUCACCAGAUUUUGUAUCUAUUGCUCAGCUAGGACCCGAGUCCAAUAGUCAAUUUAUUCUAAGCGAACAUUCAUCUCCACACUUUCCUGUCUCAAGCCCAUCCAUUAUUUCUUAACUUUUAUUUUAGCUUUCGGGGGUACAUGUUAAAGGCUUUUUAUAUAGGUAAACUCAUGUCGUGGAGGUUUGUUGUACAGAUUAUUUCAUCACCCAGGUAUUAAGCCCAGUGCCUAAUAUUGUUUUUUUCGGCUCCUCUCCCUCCUCCUACCUUCCGCCCUCAAGUAGACUCCAGUGUCUGUUAUUCCCUUCUUUGUGUUUAUGAAUUCUCAUCAUUUAGCUCCCACUUAUAAGUGAGGACAUGCAGUAUUUGGUUUUCUGUUCCCAUGUUUGCUAAGGAUAAUGGUCUCCAGUUCUACCGAUGUUCCCACAAAAGACAUAAUCUUCUUUUUUAAGGCUGCUUAGUAUUCCAUGGUAUCUAUGUAUCACAUUUUCUCUAUCCAAUCUAUUGUUGACUCACAUUUAGAUUGAUUCCAUGUUUUUGCUAUUGUGAAUAGUGCUGCAAUGAACAUUCGUGUGCAUGUGUCUUUAUGGUAGAAAGAUUUAUAUUUCUCUGAGUAUGUAUCCAGUAAUAGCCCAUUCAUUUAUUGCAUAAAAUUCUACCAAUAC